AGAGCCUGCUGGUGGCUGCCUUCUGGGCCGAGCUGAGCAGGCUUCCACACCACGCUCCACAGAACCCCCAGGGUCUCCUAAGCUUGUGCAAAACUCCAGCUGGUGGAAAGAAAGCUGGGGCAACUGCCAGAAGGAUGGCGGUGCCCUGGGAGGAAUAUUUCCGACUGGCUUUGCAAGAGAAACUGUCUACAAAGCUGCCAGAGCAGGCUGAGGAUCAUGUCCCACCAGUACUGCGUCUCCUGGAGAAGAGGCAAGAGCUGGUAGAUGCAGACCAGGCCCUGCAGGCCCAGAAGGAGGUGUUCCGCACCAAGACGGCAGCCCUGAAACAGCGUUGGGAACAGCUGGAACAAAAGGAGCGGGAGCUAAAGGGAUCGUUCAUCCGCUUUGACAAGUUUUUGCAGGACUCCGAGGCCCGGCGCAAUCGCGCGCUGCGGAGGGCGGCGGAGGAGAGGCACCAGGCGGGCCGUCGGGAGGUGGAGGCGCUGCGUCUGUGGACCCAGCUCCAGGAGCUACGGCGGGAACACGCGCGGCUGCAGCGCCGGCUUAAGCGCCUGGAGCCCUGCGCGCGCCUGCUGGAGCAAGCGCUGGAGCUGCUGCCCGGGUUCCAAGAGGUUCCGGAGCUGGUGGCGCGCUUCGACGGCCUGGCCGAGACGCAGGCGGCGCUGAGGCUCAGGGAGCGCGAGCAGCUCGCGGAGCUGGAGGCGGCGCGAGCGCGGCUGCAGCAGCUGCGGGACGCCUGGCCGGACGAGGUGCUCGCACAGGGCCAGCGGCGGGCACAGCUGCAGGAGCGCCUGGAGGCUGCCAGGGAGCGUACGCUGCAGUGGGAAUCCAAGUGGAUUCAGAUUCAGAACACAGCAGCGGAGAAGACUCUGCUCCUGGGACGCAGCAGGAUGGCUGUGCUCAACCUGUUCCAGCUAGUGUGCCAGCAUCAGGGGCAGCCUCCCACCCUGGACAUCGAGGACACGGAGGGACAGCUAGAGCACGAUUCCAACCGAAUGCCAAGAUCUGGGUCCUGGGAAUCCGCUUCGCCCCUCCUAGUUGGUUGGAUGCAUCGAUGCCACUGUUCUUCCAAGCCUGGCCUGUUACCUUGUGGCACAUGAGACUAGCAGAAACACAGGCUUGAUGUAAACAGGCAAAAGUCAGUGCCUUUUCUUUUAGUCCAACUGGAGUAGUGGAAAUUAAGAAGAAACAAAAUCUGUAACCGGUUGUAAUUAAUUCGUUGUAAACACCACUGCACUAGGACCAGACCAUCUCUUUUCAAAAUCAACUCUCUGCCCGUCAAGGAGAAAGGCUCCACGGAGGGACAUGAUGCCUUUUCCCACCUCCCCUAACACUCCCUGGCCUCCGGGCCUGGGACUCACACUGUCCUGCGGCUGCCAGAAUUCAGUAACAGCUUCAUUUGUUCAUUGCAUUAUUUUUCCAGUUGCCCCCUAGUUAUGACAAGGGGUAACUAUUUUUUUCCAUUUUUGGUGGAGAUAAAAAGUUUCCUUCUCAGCUGUUGAUACGGUGAUGAAUAUGAGGGGGAGCCCACAGAUGGUUGUAAGUUCACCCUCAAGUUCUAGUUUUUACAAUGGAUCCAUGGUAUUUAUUAAGUUCAUAUUCAUAAAGAAGUUAAUUAAAACAAAAGGAGAGCCACCCACGGAGAUAAGAGUAGGUCACAAACCAAUGAAUAUGACUGAUCCAGUUACAAGAAAAUAAAGCUGAUUGAUGUAAAUGAAAAUACUAAUUGGAUAGUGCAGGUGACAGCAGCGAGGAAGCUGUGAAGGUGUCUGCUCACGCAGCAGUUGGGAAGGUUGGCCUGAGGCUUUCAAAACCCAGAACGGUUUAGGAUCUCAGUCACCACCUCUGGGAACCACCAUCAUCACUGUUCUUUUAAUGAGGGGAUCUCCAGUCCCCGCCCUACCUUUCGGCCUCCCCCGCGUGUUGAGGGGUGGGGGCUGGACAGUGACUCUGGGGCUGGGAUGUGACUUCGUGCUGGGCCCCCCCAGGUGAAGCUGUUCAUGCAGGACCUCUCUGCCAUGCUGGCCGGCCUGGGUCAGGCUGAGCCUGCAGCCCCUGCCUCCUAGCCCUGACACAGGUGAGCAGCGGGAGAGGGAACCCCUGAGAGACCCUGAGAUAGGAGGGCCCACAUUUCCAAUGGGGUGUGGACUGAGUGGCUCUUCCUGAAUCCGUUUCCUCAUUGGGAAGAUGGGAGGGCUGUGCCUGUUCAGAGUGCUGUGGGCCUGCCAUGAGGGGCACAUAGCAAGCACUCCAUAAAUGCAGGCCCUGAUGAGGAGGUGAUGGGAAGGUCAAGGGGCUAUGUGUGGGGCAACUGCCUCUAAAAUGAGAUCAGACCAGGCCCUCCCUGCCAGGGUGGUUGGGGCAUGAAAAAAAACUCUUUGUCAGGUCUCAGAACAGGGUCCAUGCUAGAUGAGAGAUCACCAAGGCCCCCUCCACUAUGGACUCUGCCAGGUGAGGGGCCCAGCCUGAGAAUCCAGCUGCUGGGGCUGCCCUUGACCUUCUCAGAACCUCAAACAGGGGGUGGGUGGCAAGAAGACAGAGGACAGGCCAGGUUCUGACCUCCAGGUGUGGAGGGGCCGCGUUAACCUCUUCAUAGCCAGAGGGGAGCAGCUGUGUCCUUGCCCCCUGGGCUGGGCAUCCUGUUCCCCUCCCCCAGCCCACUCCCAGCUGCAACCAUGUCCAGUGGGAGGAAGGGGGACCAACUCCCGCCUCUGGCACCUGGUUUGUGCUCUGAGCUUCACUUUCCUCAUCGCUAAAUGGACAAGGCAGCAGAACUCACCCUCAGGAGACCCGCAACUCCUCUGCCACGUUAGCUGGGAUUUUAGUACCUGGGUCUCUCCAUUCCAGUUCCCCAAGUAGACCGCACUCCUGGCCACCAGCAGUGCUCAAUAAAGAUUUAUUACAUUAAAAA